AGAGCUGGCGCUCUAGCCCACGGAGUUGGUUAACUCCUCUCACCGGCCCCUGGAAAGGGUUCCAAGUGCUUUAGUACCCGACGCUGUCUGGGAAUUCCGGGCGUUUCGGCUCCUUGGUCGCAGAGGCAGGAGGGCGUGCGUGGCAGGAGGGUUCGGGUUAUAUACUCCUAGGUCCUGGGACAGAAUAGUUACGACCUCUGGGACAGGAACUCUUCUCUCUUUUGUUAAUAAACUUCCAACUCCCUCCUCAGACCCGACCGCAUGUCUGUCAUGGACCUCGCCAAUACUUGCUCCAGCUUUCAGUCGGACCUGGAUUUCUGUUCAGAUUGCGGCUCGGUCCUGCCUCUGCCCGGGGCUCAGGAUACGGUCACCUGUAUUCGCUGUGGCUUCAACAUCAACGUUCGGGACUUUGAGGGGAAGGUUGUGAAGACUUCGGUUGUGUUCCACCAACUGGGGACAGCCAUGCCUAUGUCGGUGGAGGAAGGGCCUGAGUGCCAGGGACCUGUGGUUGACAGGCGCUGCCCUCGAUGUGGUCAUGAAGGAAUGGCAUACCACACCAGACAAAUGCGUUCAGCCGAUGAAGGGCAAACUGUCUUCUACACCUGUACCAACUGCAAGUUCCAGGAGAAGGAAGACUCUUGACCUUUUUCCUGGGCAACUCUGCAGUCCCUCCCUCCUUUCGGAAGGUGAAGGAUACUGGGUUUUUAGAUGCCUUGUCCAUCCUGUCUGGUUGCAAUGUUUUGCUCCCAGAAGAGAAUCAGAUCAUCAUGUGGGGAUUACCAUUGUUCCUGGAGUACUCCUACCCUUAGUUGAAUUUCCUUAUUAAAGUUAUAUUUUUCUAUAAGACCCUGA